CUUUCCCUGCGGAGGACCAGGGCAAGUUUCCUGCCUGCACGGCACAGGAGAGCAAACUUCUACAGACAGACCAAGGCUUCCAUUUGCUGCUGACACAUGGAACUGAGGUGAAAUUGUGCUCCAUGAUUUUACAGAUUUCAUAACGUUUAAGAGACGGGACUCAGGUCAUCAAAAUGAAAGCCCUCAUCUUUGCAGCUGCUGGCCUCCUGCUUCUGUUGCCCACUUUUUGUCAGAGUGGCAUGGAAAAUGAUACAAACAACUUGGCAAAGCCAACCUUACCCAUUAAGACCUUUCGUGGAGCUCCCCCAAAUUCUUUUGAAGAGUUCCCCUUUUCUGCCUUGGAAGGCUGGACAGGAGCCACGAUUACUGUAAAAAUUAAGUGCCCUGAAGAAAGUGCUUCACAUCUCCAUGUGAAAAAUGCUACCAUGGGGUACCUGACCAGCUCCUUAAGUACUAAACUGAUACCUGCCAUCUACCUCCUGGUGUUUGUAGUUGGUGUCCCGGCCAAUGCUGUGACCCUGUGGAUGCUUUUCUUCAGGACCAGAUCCAUCUGUACCACUGUAUUCUACACCAACCUGGCCAUUGCAGAUUUUCUUUUUUGUGUUACAUUGCCCUUUAAGAUAGCUUAUCAUCUCAAUGGGAACAACUGGGUAUUUGGAGAGGUCCUGUGCCGGGCCACCACAGUCAUCUUCUAUGGCAACAUGUACUGCUCCAUUCUGCUCCUUGCCUGCAUCAGCAUCAACCGCUACCUGGCCAUCGUCCAUCCUUUCACCUACCGGGGCCUGCCCAAGCACACCUAUGCCUUGGUAACAUGUGGACUGGUGUGGGCAACAGUUUUCUUAUAUAUGCUGCCAUUUUUCAUACUGAAGCAGGAAUAUUAUCUUGUUCAGCCAGACAUCACCACCUGCCAUGAUGUUCACAACACUUGCGAGUCCUCAUCUCCCUUCCAACUCUAUUACUUCAUCUCCUUGGCAUUCUUUGGAUUCUUAAUUCCAUUUGUGCUUAUCAUCUACUGCUAUGCAGCCAUCAUCCGGACACUUAAUGCAUACGAUCAUAGAUGGUUGUGGUAUGUUAAGGCGAGUCUCCUCAUCCUUGUGAUUUUUACCAUUUGCUUUGCUCCAAGCAAUAUUAUUCUUAUUAUUCACCAUGCUAACUACUACUACAACAACACUGAUGGCUUAUAUUUUAUAUAUCUCAUAGCUUUGUGCCUGGGUAGUCUUAAUAGUUGCUUAGAUCCAUUCCUUUAUUUUCUCAUGUCAAAAACCAGAAAUCACUCCACUGCUUACCUUACAAAAUAGUGAAAUGAUCUUAGAGAACAAGGACAGCCAUCACAGAGAACGUCUGUUUUCAAGAACAACAUAAGCAUAGUGCAAGGAGCUCCAUUUCCGAGCUCCUAAGAAAUAUGCUUCAAAGGUCAAACAUUACAAAAGCAUUAGUAGUUUGUUUGUUUGUUUUUGAGACUGAGUCUCACUUUAUCACCCAGACUGGCGUGCAGUGGCACUAUCUUGGCUCAUUGCAACCUCUGCCUCCCAGGUCAGCCUCCCAAGUAGCUGGGAUUACACCACCAUGCCCAGCUACUAAAAAUACUUGUAUUUUUAGUAGAGACGGGGUUUCACCAUGUUGACCAGGCUGGUCUUGAACUCCUGACCUCAAGUGAUCUUCCGGCCUCAGCCUCCCAAAGUGCUGGAUUACAGGCGUGAGCCACUGAGCCAGCCAGCAUUAGUAAUUUUUAAAAACACUUUAUCAGUAUUUUAAAAAUGUUAAUGCAGGAGAAAAGAUAUCACAACUCUAUGGAAAAUGACAUUUCCAUUUGCCUUAUUGCUACUUCAAGCUCUUUAAAUCACCAUCUUCCCUAUUUCUGUGAGUGGUAUUGCCAUCCUUGACAUUUGACAUCAUUUUUUAUUCUUUGGUCUCUUUUGACUCUCAUGCUGGUGGCUGCCUCAUCAACUGAUUCUAUCUUUGUAGGGUCCCUCACCAGGGUCUUUUAUCUAGUUUCACCUUUGCCUUCUUUUUUCCUUUUUUUAAUAGAGACAGUGUCUCGCUUCGUCACCUGGCUGAAGUGCAGUAGCCUGAUCAUAGCUCACUUCAGCCUCCAACUCCUGGGCUCAAGCAAUCCUGCUGUCUCAGCCUCCCAAGUAACUAAGACUACAGGCAUGCACCACCAUACCCAACUAAUUUUAUUUUUUAUUUUUUGCAGAGAUGGAGUCUCACUGUUGCCCAGGCUGGUCUUGAACUCCUGGUCUCGAGUGAUCUUCCUAUCUCAGCCUCCCAAAGUGCUGGGACUACAGGCAUGAGCCACUACGUCCAGGCCACCUCUACCUUCUAACCAUUCUCUCCACUGCCAGCCUACCCUCCACCACUUCACAAGUCCUGCCAGAUUAAUCUUCCUUAGAUAUCAGUUAGGAUACAUCACUAAAACAUUUCCACUAACUCCACUGUUUCUAUAAUAAAUCAUAAAUCUUUAGCCUGGCAUUCAAGGCUAACUUGCUAAUCACACUUCCCAUUAAACCUUGCUUAUGAUAUAGGCACCAACCAAACCUCUUGCUCUGCUAUAUCUCCACUCUGCCUCAGACUGAAAAGCUAGUCCUAACGUCUUUGCCUUAAUUCUGUUCAUUUUUUCAAGUCCUUGAAGGACCAUUCUUCCCUGAUUCUCAGGCUAGAAGUGUCACUUUUCUUAUCUGUACUUCCAAAGCACUUUCGUAUAUUUUUAUUAUGGCAUUUAUAUAUAGUUCAUUUAUAUUUAAAUUUUAAUUCCAUGAACAAUCAAGUACCAAGUAUAAUGGAGAAGGUGCUCAUCCUCUGCCUUCCUUGAGCUUCUGGGUGAUGCCAGGCCCAAGUCUUUGUGGCACCCAGCUCCAUGCUUUGAAUACUAUGUGGCUGAAUGAAUUUUUAAAAUCUCAAAGCAGUUAAACAGCAGGAAAGCCCAUUAACUUCGUACUGAAAAAGCAACAUACUGUGAUGAUACGGGAUGACAUCAUUUCAGGUUGGGCAUACAAAAAAGUAAGGAAGCUAAACUAAGACUAUACUCACCAGGCCAUUUAGAAGUUUUAAAUAAUGCCUCCACUAUUUUUUUUCUUAGACAUAGCUUUUAAUGGGGAAAUGGAAUUUUGUUAUUAAUACCCAUUAUAUUCCUGUAAGUAAAUGACUAUUUUUCCCUUAACUCAGUGAUUAGACAGGAAGGAAGACAUUAGUGAUUAGACAGGAGGGAAGAUAUUAGUGAUUAGACAGCAGGGAAGAUAUUAGUGGUAAAGAGUGAAUGAUAGUAGUGAAUAUAAAUGGGGCUGAGGAAACUUUAAGCAUAAAAGAUUCCUGAGAUGACUUUACAAGUCUGUACGAAUCUGCCUUGACUGUAUAUUUCAUACUGCCCAACAAAACAAUAAAAAACAAUUUUAAAUGCA